ACCACUGGUCUUCUUGUGCUUAUCCGGGCAAGAACUUAUCGAAAUACAAUAGAAGUUUUUACUUAGAAGAGAUUUUCAGCUGCUAUGGAUUGGAUUAUGCUAUUAUGAAUAAGAAUGCUGAUGGGAGCACACACAAACCAUUUGUUCCUCAGUCCAUUUUCCUCCUCAAAAGCCUGGAAUGUGCCAUUGAUCAGUGGGAGAUGUACCUGGACAGACCCAUGAAAAGAGAUCAACAAGUUCCACCCAAGGGACCCUAUUUUUCCUAAUUUCAUUUGAAAUGGCUUCUAAUUGUCCUUCUUUCAUUCCUGCUUCCUACCAGUUUUACAGCUUUUUCUGGUUUCAAAUGUGAACUCACAUACACUCUCAUUUUUCCUCAUCACAACCCCAAGUGACCCAAUGGUCCUCACUUUCGAUAUAAGUAAAGGAGGCUCUGCAUUAAGGGCUUGUCCAAGGCACGCAGCUGAGAGGCGCUAGGACUGGCUCCAUUUCCAUCUCUAUUCUCACUGACUUUGACUACCCAGAACCCCAACAUGUGGGGCCUCAGUAUUCGAUCAAUUAUUCUAUUAAGAAGCAAAAACAAUUCCCCGCAUUGGCCCCAGUUAUUAAGCAUUUCUCAGAUUUACCUUGAGAAAUGCCCAUCGGCCUGUAUAUUCACAUCUUCACCCUUGUCCCUUCCUCCUAGAAAGGAGAAAGUCAGUUGGAUGCCCUCUGAGGAACUAGUGCAUGGCUUAACUGUCCUUCCAUGACUCCUGCCUUAUCUGUUUUCUAUUUUCCUCCUUUUCCACCGAAGUCUAUAAUCUCAAGAAAAGCAGGCACUGGCCUUAGGGCUCCUGGCCUAAGAAAUAUCAAGUCCAGUGAGAAAUCCCAUUGACUGACCCCUCCUGCUUACCCCUUUGUGAUGGAGAAGCUCCCAGGGGUUUGCUUUUUGCAUGUUACCAGGCCUAACUCAGCAUCACCAGGGGCAAGAAAAGGAAAGUAACCUAAACUAAUGCUGCUUAUAAUUGUAAUUAUUGUAAUAGUUAAUUACUGUGAUUGUACAUGUGUAACAGACAAAAUGUGUAUUUUUUUCACAGCUGCUGUGGAUUGGAUUAUGCCAUUUGGAAUAAGAAUGCUGUUAAGAGCACACAAGCCAGGUUCCUCAAGGAGAAGUGAAAUGACAACCUCACUAGAUACAGUUGAGACCUUUGGUACCACAUCCUACUAUGAUGACGUGGGCCUGCUCUGUGAAAAAGCUGAUACCAGAGCACUGAUGGCCCAGUUUGUGCCCCCGCUGUACUCCCUGGUGUUCACUGUGGGCCUCUUGGGCAAUGUGGUGGUGGUGAUGAUCCUCAUAAAAUACAGGAGGCUCCGAAUUAUGACCAACAUCUACCUGCUCAACCUGGCCAUUUCGGACCUGCUCUUCCUCGUCACCCUUCCAUUCUGGAUCCACUAUGUCAGGGGGCAUAACUGGGUUUUUGGCCAUGGCAUGUGUAAGCUCCUCUCAGGGUUUUAUCACACAGGCUUGUACAGCGAGAUCUUUUUCAUAAUCCUGCUGACAAUCGACAGGUACCUGGCCAUUGUCCAUGCUGUGUUUGCCCUUCGAGCCCGGACUGUCACUUUUGGUGUCAUCACCAGCAUCGUCACCUGGGGCCUGGCAGUGCUAGCAGCUCUUCCUGAAUUUAUCUUCUAUGAGACUGAAGAGUUGUUUGAAGAGACUCUUUGCAGUGCUCUUUACCCAGAGGAUACAGUAUAUAGCUGGAGGCAUUUCCACACUCUGAGAAUGACCAUCUUCUGUCUCGUUCUCCCUCUGCUCGUUAUGGCCAUCUGCUACACAGGAAUCAUCAAAACGCUGCUGAGGUGCCCCAGUAAAAAAAAGUACAAGGCCAUCCGGCUCAUUUUUGUCAUCAUGGCGGUGUUUUUCAUUUUCUGGACACCCUACAAUGUGGCUAUCCUUCUCUCUUCCUAUCAAUCCAUCUUAUUUGGAAAUGACUGUGAGCGGAGCAAGCAUCUGGACCUGGUCAUGCUGGUGACAGAGGUGAUCGCCUACUCCCACUGCUGCAUGAACCCGGUGAUCUACGCCUUUGUUGGAGAGAGGUUCCGGAAGUACCUGCGCCACUUCUUCCACAGGCACUUGCUCAUGCACCUGGGCAGAUACAUCCCAUUCCUUCCUAGUGAGAAGCUGGAAAGAACCAGCUCUGUCUCUCCAUCCACAGCAGAGCCGGAACUCUCUAUUGUGUUUUAGGUCAGAUGCAGAAAAUUGCCUAAAGAGGAAGGACCAAGGAGAUGAAGCAAACACAUUAAGCCUUCCACACUCACCUCUAAAACAGUCCUUCAAACUUCCAGUGCAACACUGAAGCUCUUGAAGACACUGAAAUAUACACACAGCAGUAGCAGUAGAUGCAUGUACCCUAAGGUCAUUACCACAGGCCAGGGGCUGGGCAGCGUACUCAUCAUCAACCCUAAAAAGCAGAGCUUUGCUUCUCUCUCUAAAAUGAGUUACCUACAUUUUAAUGCACCUGAAUGUUAGAUAGUUACUAUAUGCCGCUACAAAAAGGUAAAACUUUUUAUAUUUUAUACAUUAACUUCAGCCAGCUAUUGAUAUAAAUAAAACAUUUUCACACAAUACAAUAAGUUAACUAUUUUAUUUUCUAAUGUGCCUAGUUCUUUCCCUGCUUAAUGAAAAGCUUGUUUUUUCAGUGUGAAUAAAUAAUCGUAAGCAACA